ACACUCUGCGUGUUUUUGUGUCCUGCCAGGCACCGUGGUCUCAUCCGCCUGCACAGCUGAGUCCAGUGGGAGCUGACGCCAUGACCCUCACCCUCUCAGUCCUGAUUUGCCUCGGGCUGAGUGUGGGCCCCAGGACCUGCGUGCAGGCAGGCACCCUCCCCAAACCCACCCUCUGGGCUGAGCCAGCCUCUGUGAUAGCUCGGGGGAAGCCCGUGACCCUCUGGUGUCAGGGGCCCCUGGAGACUGAGGAGUACCGUCUGGAUAAGGAGGGACUCCCAUGGGCCCGGAAGAGACAGAACCCACUGGAGCCUGGAGCCAAGGCCAAGUUCCACAUUCCAUCCACGGUGUAUGACAGUGCAGGGCGAUACCGCUGCUACUAUGAGACCCCUGCAGGCUGGUCAGAGCCCAGUGACCCCCUGGAGCUGGUGGCGACAGGAUUCUAUGCAGAACCCACUCUUUUAGCCCUGCCGAGUCCUGUGGUGGCCUCAGGAGGAAAUGUGACCCUCCAGUGUGAUACACUGGACGGACUUCUCACGUUUGUUCUUGUUGAGGAAGAACAGAAGCUCCCCAGGACCCUGUACUCACAGAAGCUCCCCAAAGGGCCAUCCCAGGCCCUGUUCCCUGUGGGUCCCGUGACCCCCAGCUGCAGGUGGAGGUUCAGAUGCUAUUACUAUUACAGGAAAAACCCUCAGGUGUGGUCGAACCCCAGUGACCUCCUGGAGAUUCUGGUCCCAGGCGUGUCUAGGAAGCCCUCCCUCCUGAUCCCGCAGGGCUCUGUCGUGGCCCGCGGAGGCAGCCUGACCCUGCAGUGUCGCUCUGAUGUCGGCUAUGACAUAUUCGUUCUGUACAAGGAGGGGGAACAUGACCUCGUCCAGGGCUCUGGCCAGCAGCCCCAGGCUGGGCUCUCCCAGGCCAACUUCACCCUGGGCCCUGUGAGCCGCUCCCACGGGGGCCAGUACAGAUGCUACGGUGCACACAACCUCUCCCCUAGGUGGUCGGCCCCCAGCGACCCCCUGGACAUCCUGAUCGCAGGACUGAUCCCUGACAUACCCGCCCUCUCGGUGCAGCCGGGCCCCAAGGUGGCCUCAGGAGAGAACGUGACCCUGCUGUGUCAGUCAUGGCAUCAGAUAGACACUUUCUUUUUGACCAAGGAGGGGGCAGCCCAUCCCCCGCUGUGUCUAAAGUCAAAGUACCAGUCUUAUAGACACCAGGCUGAAUUCUCCAUGAGUCCUGUGACCUCAGCCCAGGGUGGAACCUACCGAUGCUACAGCGCAAUCAGGUCCUACCCCUACCUGCUGUCCAGCCCUAGUUACCCCCAGGAGCUCGUGGUCUCAGGACCCUCUGGGGAUCCCAGCCUCUCACCUACAGGCUCCACCCCCACACCUGCAGGCCCUGAGGACCAGCCCCUCACCCCCACGGGGUUGGAUCCCCAGAGUGGUCUGGGAAGGCACCUGGGGGUUGUGACUGGGGUCUCAGUGGCCUUCGUCCUGCUGCUGUUCCUCCUCCUCUUCCUCCUCCUCCGACAUCGGCAUCAGAGCAAACACAGGACAUCGGCCCAUUUCUACCGUCCUGCAGGGGCUGCGGGGCCAGAGCCCAAGGACCAGGGCCUGCAGAAGAGGGCCAGCCCAGUUGCUGACAUCCAGGAGGAAAUUCUCAAUGCUGCCGUGAAGGACACACAGCCCAAGGACGGGGUGGAGAUGGAUGCUCGGGCUGCUGCAUCUGAAGCCCCCCAGGAUGUGACCUACGCCCAGCUACACAGCUUGACCCUCAGACGGGAGGCAACUGAGCCUCCUCCAUCCCAGGAAAGGGAACCUCCAGCUGAACCCAGCAUCUACGCCCCCCUGGCCAUCCACUAGCCCACGGGGGACCCAGAUCUCAUACUCAACAGAAGGAGACUCAGAGACUCCAGAAGGCACAGGAGCUGCCCCCAGUGGACACCAAUGAACCCCAGCCAGCCUGGACCCCUAACAAAGACCACCAGGACAUCCUGGGAACUCUGGGACUCACUAGAUUCUGCAGUCAAAGAUGACUAAUAUCCUUGCAUUUUUGAAAUGAAGCCACAGACUUCUCAAUAAAUCAAUGAGCUGAGAAAACUGAAACAGAAAUUAGAGCAUGGUAUAAAUUUGGAAUGAUAAUGUAAAUAUUACACAUUAAAUGAUGAAAUCGGAAAACUACAAAUGAGCGAAUGAAUUAGAAAAGAAUAAAACCUACGUAAUUAAUGACCUUGGCAAUGACAGAAAGAAUUUAGAAAAAGAACAACAAAUUAUUCCAAAUGAAGGUGUGAGGAAGGGGACAAAAAUAACAAGAGGAGUUACUAAUGAGGGCUACGUGAAAACUCGAUGAAGCCAAAAAAGCUCAUUCUUGAGAAUGUGAAUUACAUUCACAAAUCCUAGCCACAAUAAGCAAGGAAAAAAGCGGGGUUCAGGCACACAUUUCCAUAUGGGGGUGAAACAGCAGACACCACCACAAAUCUGACACAUAUUGCCUUUAUUUUUUUCACUUUUAAGUUCAGGGAUACAUGUGCAGGUUUGUUAGACAGAUAAACUUGUGUCAAGGGGAUUUGUCUUGGUUUUUGUGUGAGGGUUUUUGUUUUGUUUUGUUUUGUUUUGUUUUUUGAGACGGAGUCUCGCUCUAUCACCCAGGCUGGAGUACAGUGGAGUGAUCUCGGCUCACUGCAACCUCUGCCUCCCGGGUUCAAGCGAUUCUCCUGCCUCAGUCUCCCGAGUAACUGGGACUACAGGCACCUGCCACCACGCCCGGCUAAUUUUUGUAUUUUUAGUAGAGACAGGGUUUCUCCAUGUUGGUCAGGCUGGUCUCAAACUCCCGACCUCAGGUGAUCCGCCCGCCUCAGCCUCCCAAAGUGCUGGGCUUACAGGCGUGAGCCACCACGUCCAGCCCAUACAUUUCAAUUUUAAAGGGAUGCGCCCUAGUCCUUAGUUAGUCUCUCCUCAUCUCUAUAAAAUGUUCAGCUACUCACCUCUUGGGCUAUUGCUAGACAUCGUUUUCUCUUCCUUCUUUCUGACGCCUACAAUAGAUAGGACAUUCCCCCUCCUCAUUCUAUUCUCCCAAGUACUUUAAAUUGCAAUUUAUAAAGUUUCUAUGCUACACUCUAAAAAAAAUUCUGUUUUGUUUUCUAAUUUCAUAAUUGGUGCUUCACUGUGUCUUGUCCUCGAAGGAAUGAGUAUUUUGAUUGUGUUCAUUAAAUCUGAUUUUUCUAUGUCUUCUAA